CUCUGCUGCGCGCCGCGAGUGGGAGGGGGGACUUUAGAAGCGGGGAGAGCAGGAGACUUUUGGGGAGCAGGCCCCAGGGGCGCCGCCCCGCCCCCAGGCCCCACAUACCCCUCCCCUCCGGGUAGCCCCCUCUGUGGCUGCGCCCGCGCCCCUCGCCCCGGCGGGCAGUCCUCAGGCCCCGCGCCCGGCCGGCGGGGGUGGGGGCGGCGGGGAGCGGGCACGUGGCUCGGGGUCCGGCCGGCCCGCCCCCCGGCGCCGGCCAGUCCCCGCGGUGUCCGCGGCCGCGGGGGCAGCGGGAGAGAGGGCGGGGCGGCGCGGGCAGCGCGGGGAGGGGGUCGCGCGGGGGCGGGCCGCAGCUGGGCGGGGGUCGGCGGGCUUCCGGGCGGCGGCGGCGGGCGCGGCGCGAUGUGCGAGCGGGCGGCGCGCCUGUGCAGGGCCGGCGCGCACAGGCUGCUCCGGGAGCCGCCGCAGCAGGGCCGGGCGCUGGGCGGGCUGCUGCGCUGGGUGGGCGCCAGGAUGGGCGAGCCCCGGGAGUCGCUGGCCCCCGCCGCCCCCGCGGACCCCGGCCCAGCCUCGCCGCGCGGGGGCACCGCCGUCAUCCUGGACAUUUUCCGCCGUGCGGACAAAAAUGAUGAUGGGAAGCUGUCCUUGGAGGAAUUCCAGCUCUUCUUUGCAGAUGGCGUCCUUAAUGAGAAAGAACUGGAGGAUCUCUUUCACACGAUUGACUCUGACAACACCAACCAUGUGGACACCAAGGAGCUGUGUGAUUACUUUGUGGACCACAUGGGUGACUAUGAGGAUGUCCUGGCCUCCCUGGAGACCUUGAAUCACUCUGUCCUGAAGGCCAUGGGUUAUACCAAGAAGGUAUAUGAGGGUGGGAGCAACGUGGACCAGUUUGUGACCCGCUUCCUCCUGAAGGAGACGGCCAAUCAGAUCCAGUCGCUGCUGAGCUCAGUGGAGAGUGCGGUGGAGGCCAUCGAGGAACAGACCAGCCAGCUCCGACAGAACCACAUCAAACCCAGCCACAGCGCGGCACAGACCUGGUGUGGAAGCCCCACUCCCGCCUCUGCCCCCAACCACAAGCUCAUGGCUAUGGAACAAGGCAAGACCCUUCCAUCUGCCACGGAGGAUGCAAAGGAAGAGGGUCUGGAAGCCCAGAUCAGCCGCUUGGCAGAGCUGAUUGGGAGGCUGGAGAGCAAAGCACUGUGGUUCGACCUGCAGCAGCGCCUGUCAGAUGAAGAUGGCACCAACAUGCACCUGCAGCUGGUCCGGCAGGAGAUGGCCGUGUGCCCCGAGCAACUGAGCGAGUUUCUGGACUCUCUGCGCCAGUAUCUGCGGGGGACCACUGGCGUGAGGAACUGCUUCCACAUCACUGCCGUGAGGCUCUCAGAUGGCUUCACCUUUGUCAUCUAUGAGUUCUGGGAGACAGAGGAGGCGUGGAAGAGGCACCUGCAGAGCCCCCUGUGUAAGGCGUUCCGGCACGUCAAGGUGGACACACUGAGCCAGCCUGAGGCCCUCUCCAGGAUCUUGGUGCCAGCUGCUUGGUGCACGGUGGGACGGGACUGACAGCCUCCCAGAGGCCCGUGGAGGAGCCCACCAGCCCCUUCUUCUUGUGAAGGAAAUCCCGUUUUUUUCUAGACAGACACUUUGGUGCAGAAGCUUCUUUUCAAUCCAUCCUCCACAAGAAGGUGUUUCCCUGUUGUUAAGUGAAGGAGGCCGCCCCUGCCCCCACCUGAGAAGGCAGAGCAGUGUCUGUGCUGCCAGGUCCUGGUGAAGCCCAAGGUUGAAGGGGGCGGCUUCCUGGAGCCAGCACCCCUGCCUCCUGGUCCUGGCCUCUCCCCUACCCCUCACAUGGCCACGCAUGACCCACACUGACCACACCCUGCCCUCUUCGGUGACAUUCUUCUACCUAGUAGGAGUCAUGCCCCUGUAGUGCCCAACCUAGCCAGGUAGCCACCACUGUGCCCAGGCGCCAAAUAAACCCUGGUUGGGAAGA